CUCUUUCGGCCGCGCUGGUGAACAGGUAGGUCAUCCUUGCGGCCUUGCGGCAUGGGCAGUAUCCGCCGCCAUCCUCUUCCGUGAGGCGCGCUGAGACCCGGACCGGCCCUCCUGAGAGGAUGCCGGUGCGGGCGCCCGCGGAGAGGGUAGGGAGUGGUGGGCGCGGCGGCCUCGGGGGCGGGGUCCCGGAAAGCCGGGCUGGCGGGGGUACCCGGGCCGCCCGGCCGCGCUAAUCGUGAGUCGCCCCCAGGACCCGUCGCCAUGGGCCGUGUGAUCCGUGGACAGAGGAAGGGCGCCGGGUCUGUGUUCCGCGCGCACGUGAAGCACCGUAAAGGCGCUGCGCGCCUGCGCGCCGUGGAUUUCGCUGAGCGGCACGGCUACAUCAAGGGCAUCGUCAAGGACAUCAUCCACGACCCGGGCCGCGGCGCGCCCCUCGCCAAGGUGGUCUUCCGGGAUCCGUAUCGGUUUAAGAAGCGGACGGAGCUGUUCAUUGCCGCCGAGGGCAUUCACACGGGCCAGUUUGUGUAUUGCGGCAAGAAGGCCCAGCUCAACAUUGGCAAUGUGCUCCCUGUGGGCACCAUGCCUGAGGGUACAAUCGUGUGCUGCCUGGAGGAGAAGCCUGGAGACCGUGGCAAGCUGGCCCGGGCAUCAGGGAACUAUGCCACCGUUAUCUCCCACAACCCUGAGACCAAGAAGACCCGUGUGAAGCUGCCCUCCGGCUCCAAGAAGGUUAUCUCCUCAGCCAACAGAGCUGUGGUUGGUGUGGUGGCUGGAGGUGGCCGAAUUGACAAACCCAUCUUGAAGGCUGGCCGGGCGUACCACAAAUAUAAGGCAAAGAGGAACUGCUGGCCACGAGUACGGGGUGUGGCCAUGAAUCCUGUGGAGCAUCCUUUUGGAGGUGGCAACCACCAGCACAUCGGCAAGCCCUCCACCAUCCGCAGAGAUGCCCCUGCUGGCCGCAAAGUGGGUCUCAUUGCUGCCCGCCGGACUGGACGUCUCCGGGGAACCAAGACUGUGCAGGAGAAAGAGAACUAGUGCUGAGGGCCUCAAUAAAGUUUGUGUUUAUGCCA